AUCCAUGGCACGGAGCGGCGGCGGCGGCGGCAGCAGGAGCCCGGCGCGAUCCGCUAGGUCCCAGCCCAGCGCCCAGCGAGCAGGCGACGCGGAGGGGCCGGGCCUCCAGUGUCCCGAGGGCCGGGCGCUGAGACUCCGGCCGCGCAGCUGGGAGCUGCCCGCGCUGCGCUGACAGCCGCGCCGACGUCCUCCCCGCCGGGGCGCUCGCAGGACAUGCCCCCGGGGCGCGGCGGCGGGGACCCCGGGGCUCGCCUCCGCCCAGGGCCCCCCUCCACGCCCUCGGGAGCCCCGGGCCCCCGCUGAGCACUCCUCCCGCACGCCUGGGUCCCUCCGGCCGGCGCGCAGCCCGGCCCCAGCGCUGUGGGUCCCCGCGGGGCGAUGGGUUGAUGGGCGCCGGGGGACGCAGGAUGCGGGGGGCGCCCGCGCGCCUGCUGCUGCCGCUGCUGCCGUGGCUCCUGCUGCUCCUGGCGCCCGAGGCUCGGGGCGCGCCCGGCUGCCCGCUAUCCAUCCGCAGCUGCAAGUGCUCGGGGGAGCGGCCCAAGGGGCUGAGCGGCGGCGUCCCUGGCCCGGCUCGGCGGAGGGUGGUGUGCAGCGGCGGGGACCUCCCGGAGCCUCCCGAGCCCGGCCUUCUGCCUAACGGCACCGUUACCCUGCUCUUGAGCAAUAACAAGAUCACGGGGCUCCGCAAUGGCUCCUUCCUGGGACUGUCACUGCUGGAGAAGCUGGACCUGAGGAACAACAUCAUCAGCACAGUGCAGCCGGGCGCCUUCCUGGGCCUGGGGGAGCUGAAGCGUUUAGAUCUCUCCAACAACCGGAUUGGCUGUCUCACCUCCGAGACCUUCCAGGGCCUCCCCAGGCUUCUCCGACUAAACAUAUCUGGAAACAUCUUCUCCAGUCUGCAACCUGGGGUCUUUGAUGAGCUGCCAGCCCUUAAGGUUGUGGACUUGGGCACCGAGUUCCUGACCUGUGACUGCCACCUGCGCUGGCUGCUGCCCUGGGCCCAGAAUCGCUCCCUGCAGCUGUCGGAACACACGCUCUGUGCUUACCCCAGUGCCCUGCAUGCUCAGGCCCUGGGCAGCCUCCAGGAGGCCCAGCUCUGCUGCGAGGGGGCCCUGGAGCUGCACACACACCACCUCAUCCCGUCCCUACGCCAAGUGGUGUUCCAGGGGGAUCGGCUGCCCUUCCAGUGCUCUGCCAGCUACCUGGGCAACGACACCCGCAUCCGCUGGUACCACAACCGAGCCCCUGUGGAGGGUGAUGAGCAGGCGGGCAUCCUCCUGGCCGAGAGCCUCAUCCACGACUGCACCUUCAUCACCAGUGAGCUGACGCUGUCUCACAUCGGCGUGUGGGCCUCAGGCGAGUGGGAGUGCACCGUGUCCAUGGCCCAAGGCAACGCCAGCAAGAAGGUGGAGAUCGUGGUGCUGGAGACCUCUGCCUCCUACUGCCCCGCCGAGCGUGUUGCCAACAACCGCGGGGACUUCAGGUGGCCCCGAACUCUGGCUGGCAUCACAGCCUACCAGUCCUGCCUGCAGUAUCCCUUCACCUCAGUGCCCCUGGGCGGGGGUGCCCCGGGCACCCGAGCCUCCCGCCGGUGUGACCGUGCCGGCCGCUGGGAGCCAGGGGACUACUCCCACUGUCUCUACACCAACGACAUCACCAGGGUGCUGUACACCUUCGUGCUGAUGCCCAUCAAUGCCUCCAAUGCGCUGACCCUGGCUCACCAGCUGCGCGUGUACACAGCCGAGGCCGCUAGCUUUUCAGACAUGAUGGAUGUAGUCUAUGUGGCUCAGAUGAUCCAGAAAUUUUUGGGUUAUGUCGACCAGAUCAAAGAGCUGGUAGAGGUGAUGGUGGACAUGGCCAGCAACCUGAUGCUGGUGGACGAGCACCUGCUGUGGCUGGCCCAGCGCGAGGACAAGGCCUGCAGCCGCAUCGUGGGUGCCCUGGAGCGCAUUGGGGGGGCCGCCCUCAGCCCCCAUGCCCAGCACAUCUCAGUGAAUGCGAGGAACGUGGCAUUGGAGGCCUACCUCAUCAAGCCGCACAGCUACGUGGGCCUGACCUGCACAGCCUUCCAGAGGAGGGAGGGAGGGGUGCCGGGCACACGGCCAGGAAGCCCUGGCCAGAACCCCCCACCUGAGCCCGAGCCCCCAGCUGACCAGCAGCUCCGCUUCCGCUGCACCACCGGGAGGCCCAAUGUUUCUCUGUCGUCCUUCCACAUCAAGAACAGCGUGGCCCUGGCCUCCAUCCAGCUGCCCCCGAGUCUAUUCUCAUCCCUUCCGGCUGCCCUGGCUCCCCCGGUGCCCCCAGACUGCACCCUGCAACUGCUCGUCUUCCGAAAUGGCCGCCUCUUCCACAGCCACAGCAACACCUCCCGCCCUGGAGCUGCUGGGCCUGGCAAGAGGCGUGGCGUGGCCACCCCCGUCAUCUUCGCAGGAACCAGUGGCUGUGGCGUGGGAAACCUGACAGAGCCAGUGGCCGUUUCGCUGCGGCACUGGGCUGAGGGAGCCGAACCUGUGGCCGCUUGGUGGAGCCAGGAGGGGCCCGGGGAGGCUGGGGGCUGGACCUCGGAGGGCUGCCAGCUCCGCUCCAGCCAGCCCAAUGUCAGCGCCCUGCACUGCCAGCACUUGGGCAAUGUGGCCGUGCUCAUGGAGCUGAGCGCCUUUCCCAGGGAGGUGGGGGGCGCCGGGGCAGGGCUGCACCCCGUGGUAUACCCCUGCACGGCCUUGCUGCUGCUCUGCCUCUUCGCCACCAUCAUCACCUACAUCCUCAACCACAGCUCCAUCCGUGUGUCCCGGAAAGGCUGGCACAUGCUGCUGAACUUGUGCUUCCACAUAGCCAUGACCUCUGCUGUCUUUGCGGGGGGCAUCACACUCACCAACUACCAGAUGGUCUGCCAGGCGGUGGGCAUCACCCUGCACUACUCCUCCCUAUCCACGCUGCUCUGGAUGGGCGUGAAGGCGCGAGUGCUCCAUAAGGAGCUCACCUGGAGGGCACCCCCUCCGCAAGAAGGGGACCCCGCUCUGCCUACUCCCAGUCCUAUGCUCCGGUACAUACUUUCAAUUCCAGCUUUGCAAUUGGGGAGGGACUCCAACGCAGGCGUAGGAAACCUCCCAAGGUUCUAUUUGAUCGCUGGAGGGAUUCCACUCAUUAUCUGUGGCAUCACAGCUGCAGUCAACAUCCACAACUACCGGGACCACAGCCCCUACUGCUGGCUGGUGUGGCGUCCAAGCCUUGGCGCCUUCUACAUCCCUGUGGCUUUGAUUCUGCUCAUCACCUGGAUCUAUUUCCUGUGCGCCGGGCUACGCUUACGGGGUCCUCUGGCACAGAACCCCAAGGCGGGCAACAGCAGGGCCUCCCUGGAGGCAGGGGAGGAGCUGAGGGGUUCCACCAGGCUCAGGGGCAGCGGCCCCCUCCUGAGUGACUCAGGUUCCCUUCUUGCUACUGGGAGCGCGCGAGUGGGGACGCCCGGGCCCCCGGAGGAUGGUGACAGCCUCUAUUCUCCGGGAGUCCAGCUAGGGGCGCUGGUGACCACGCACUUCCUGUACUUGGCCAUGUGGGCCUGCGGGGCUCUGGCAGUGUCCCAGCGCUGGCUGCCCCGGGUGGUGUGCAGCUGCUUGUACGGGGUGGCAGCCUCCGCCCUGGGCCUCUUCGUCUUCACUCACCACUGUGCCAGGCGGAGGGACGUGAGAGCCUCGUGGCGCGCCUGCUGCCCCCCUGCCUCUCCCGCGGCCCCCCAUGCCCCGCCCCGGGCCCUGCCCGCCGCCGCAGAGGACGGUUCCCCGGUGUUCGGGGAGGGCCCCCCCUCCCUCAAGUCCUCCCCAAGCGGCAGCAGCGGCCAUCCGCUGGCUCUGGGCCCCUGCAAGCUCACCAACCUGCAGCUGGCCCAGAGUCAGGUGUGCGAGGCGGGGGCGGCGGCCGGCGGGGAAGGAGAGCCGGAGCCGGCGGGCACCCGGGGAAACCUCGCCCACCGCCACCCCAACAACGUGCACCACGGGCGUCGGGCGCACAAGAGCCGGGCCAAGGGACACCGCGCGGGGGAGGCCUGCGGCAAGAACCGGCUCAAGGCCCUGCGCGGGGGCGCGGCGGGGGCGCUGGAGCUGCUGUCCAGCGAGAGCGGCAGUCUGCACAACAGCCCCACCGACAGCUACCUGGGCAGCAGCCGCAACAGCCCGGGCGCCGGCCUGCAGCUGGAAGGCGAGCCCAUGCUCACGCCGUCCGAGGGCAGCGACACCAGCGCCGCGCCGCUUUCUGAGGCGGGCCGGGCAGGCCAGCGCCGCAGCGCCAGCCGCGACAGUCUCAAGGGCGGCGGCGCGCUGGAGAAGGAGAGCCAUCGCCGCUCGUACCCGCUCAACGCCGCCAGCCUAAACGGCGCCCCCAAGGGGGGCAAGUACGACGACGUCACCCUGAUGGGCGCGGAGGUAGCCAGCGGCGGCUGCAUGAAGACCGGACUCUGGAAGAGCGAAACUACCGUCUAAGGUGGGGCGGGCGACGCGGUAGACGGGCUGGCCACGCGGCUCGUUCCCCCGCUCCUCGGGGCCCUCCAAGGUGUCUCCGUAGUCAGCAGGUUGGAGGCAGAGGAGCCGAUGGCUGGAGGAAGCCCACAGGCGGAUGUUCCCCACUUGCCUAGAGGGCAUCCCUCUGGGGUAGCGACAGACAAUCCCAGAAACACGCAUAAUACAUUUCCGUCCAGCCCGGGGCAGUCUGACUGUCGGUGCCCUCCCAGGAACGGGGAAGGCCUCCGUCUGUGUGAAAGGGCACAGCACAUCCCAGGUGCACCCUCCCCAAGUACUCCCACCCCGCCUACUGUCCAUGCGGCCUCACUGGGGGCCAUCAGCCUCACCAGCAAAGCAGAGAUGAGAGCGUGGGAACUGUGUUCUUUCCUCCCUGCCCUCUACUGAUUUCAGCCCAGCCCCUGCCUAGAUCCUAGGUCCCUUUUCCUCCCGAGUUUGGCUGGCACGAGAGCUAGCCCAGCACAUGAAGCAGGUGAUGUUAAGUCACAAGGUGCUGCUUUUCAGAUCCACUAUGCAAGAGGGGAGGGUGGGGCCACGUGAAAGGCAGCUCUAGACAUCAACCAGUCCUGGGGGAGGGGAGUGGGAACCGGGCACAACUAGGAACAAUGCCACCAUUCCCACAGGAGUGGUACUUAAACCAGACAGCAGGGUUCAGAGGUGGCACACCGGGACAAAGCUGAGGCCCUGCACCUCAACAGCUGACUGCCAGGUGCCUGUGGGUGAACUGAGGGGAGUAGAGGGAGAGGGCAGGUGGAACUGGGGCAGAAUCUAGUCAUGCCCUAAAGCUAGUCCUGUAAACAAUGGUGCCCCAGAAAGCUGCAGGUGGUGUUUGGAGAAGCAGUUACUUUUCAGUUACAAGACCCAUCUCCCUAGUCUCAGCCUUACAACACCACGGGACUAAGGAAGAGCACUUCCUUGCCUCCGUAAGGCCAGAGGAAGAACCAUCCCAAUCAUUUGAUCUCCAGCUCCACAGUAGAGAGAAACCUACAAAAUGUCAAACCAGCUUCCCGACUCCCAGGAGCUCAAGCCAAGCCCAGAGGCAGUGGCUGGGGUCCCUGCAGGUCAUGAGGGGCCUAUGCCUUUACUCCUUUUAAACACCAGCACCCGUCUUUUCCCCAACCUAAAACCAACCACCAGCAUUUCACUACAGGACCAAAUGGAAACCGAGGGAACCCUGGGUCUUGGGAAGAACAACAGGAAACCAAGGUCUGACCUAGGGUUCCCUCCCAGUCUUCACAUCACUCUGGCCUCAUCACCAAGGUGACAGAGGACACAGGGGAGGGGGAAAACCCACACACACUCCUUGGAAUGGGUCCUGUUAUUUAUGCUUGCUGCACAGACAUAUUAGAAGAAAAAAAAAAGCUUUGUAUUAUUCUUCCACAUAUGCUGGCUGCUGUUUACACACCCUGCCAAUGCCUUAGCACUGGAGAGCUUUUUGCAAUAUGCUGGGGAAAGGGGAGGGAGGGAAUGAAAGUGCCAAAGAAAACAUGUUUUUAAGAACUCGGGUUUUAUACAAUAGAAUGUUUUCUAGCAGAUGCCUCUUGUUUUAAUAUAUUAAAAUUUUGCAAAGCCCUUUGAGCUACUGCCUUAGUCUACCCACUGUCCUUUUGUUAUGAGGUAGAGGAUCUCAUGACACCAUACACACAAACCCAUCAUUGCCUGUGAAUGCACGUAGGGCCAGAAUUCCCCAGUUCCCGCUCCUCUGAGGGUUGAUACUGCUGGGAAUGCCAACCACUCCACAAGCAGAGGGAAGCCCCCUCAGGCCUGCAGGAGGAGCCGCAGCAGUGUGUCCAAUUCAAACCAGCAGCAAAGAGCCUGACAUUUUCCCAUCCAUCUAUGAGGAAAGCCAUCUCACAGAACAUGGACAUAGGCAACUUGCUCUCCCACACCAAGGGAUGGGAAUCUCUCCUACCUAUAGUCAUCCCUGCACUCCUGACUUUACUCCAGGACCCAGGGUCCAACUAAUGGCAGAGCCCCUCUUGGUUCCUUCAAACAAGAAAAGCAAUACCUACGGACUGGUGUACACUUCCAUCCUUGGUUAUAACAGGAAUGUUAUCAAGCUGUCAGAACAGGAUGAAGUGCUCCCAGUGGAUAUCCAUCAGGGAGGGUUAGGGACACUCGUGGCAGCCUGUCUAGCAGCCUGGGCUCUCUGAAAGUCCCUAACUUCCUGAGGGGUACGCAAAUACUGUUCUAUUUCACUAUCAGAAAUGUUCUCAUCUCCAGUGACAGUGGAGACAGGGGGUACAGGGCAGAUCCGCUUCGGGGACUUCAACAUGCAGGGUGGCAAGAGAAGGGCAGGACUGGCCGGCCGCUUCCCCUGGGGUAAACCUAAGGAAUUAUUUCCCACCUCCCCUUCUCCUUGCCCCUGUCCCCACCCCGGUGGCUCCUUCUCUCGGGUCUCCACUUCUGCUGUCCCAUCCCGAAAGGCAGAGCGGACCAGUGACUGGCGGUGCUGGAGAAGGUCACCGAUGUGCUUCACCACAGACCGUUUGUCAAGUCUCAGAA